UAUAAACUUCCUGAUUUGUAUUUGACAUCUCAAAGAAAGGAGACCAGAAUUCAAUGAUACUUUGGAUUUCACAGAGUUCAAUUUUCUGCCCAGCCAUUAUGUUUAUGAAGUUGAGUAUUUUUGAAUGGUCAUAGUUGUGGUUACUGUUGAGAGGUGUCCAUCCUUUUUCUGGCUUAAGAUUGUUAGGACCUUUGUAGGAAGCAGUGGUUCUUUUUUUUUUUUUUUUUGAGACGGAGUCUCGCUCUGUUGCUCAGGCUGGAGUGCAGUGGCAUGAUCUCGGCUUACUGCAUGCUCUGCCUUGCGGGUUUACACCAUUCUCCUGCCUCAGCCUUCUGAGUAGCUGGGACUACAGGCACCUGCCACCACUCCGGGCUAAUUUUUUGUAUUUUUAGUAGAGAUGGGGUUUCACCAUGUUAGCCAGGAUGGUCUCGAUCUCCUGACCUCGUGAUCCGCCCGCCUUGGCCUCCCAACGUGGCCGGAAGCAGUGGUUCUUAAGCUUUAGCAAGCAUUGGAAAUGGUUGGAGGGCUUGCUGAAGCACAUAUGGCUGCCUCCCAGUUUCUGAUUUAAUAGGUCUGGGGUACCGAUAAUUUGCAUUUUUAACAAUGAUAUGGUUUGGCUGUGUCCCCACCCAAAUCUCAUCUUGAAUUCCCACGUGUUGUGGGAGGGACCCAGUGGGAGGUAAUUGAAUUUUGGGGGCAGGUGUUCCCCAUGCUGUUCUUGUGAUAGUGAAUAAGUCUCAUGAGAUCUGAUGGUUUUGGGAAAGGGGAGUCUUCCUGCACAAGCUCUCUCUUUGCCUGCUGUCAUCCAUGUAAGACGUGAUUGCUCCUGUUUGUCUUCCGCCAUGAUUGUGAGGCUUCCCCAGCCAUGUGGAAAUGUAAGUCCGAUUAAACCUCUUUCCUGUGUAAAUUGCCCAGUCUCGGGUAUGUCUUUAUCAGCAGCAUGAAAAUGGACUAACACAAACAAGUUCCCAGGUGAUGCUGAAGCUGCUAGUCCUGGGACCACACCAACACCCACUGUUCUAGGGCACUGGGCAGAGACAGAUAAGCUUGUACCAGCAUCAUGUGGAAGACAAAAUGGAACUCAAAGCCCUAUUAACCCUGGUUGGCUUUAUCUUUCCCCUGACCCUGUGCUUAAGUUCACUUUCUCUCUAGCUCUUCCUGCUCUUGUUCCCUUCUUGUGUACCUGAACUACAUUUAACAUCCUGACUCAAAACAGCCGAGUUUCUAACCAUGCUACUUGUUAUUGUACCAUUUCCUUUCUAACCCAGAUUAUCAUCUCUGUUUCAAAUUUCUUGCUGUGGUAACCUCACCUUAAUUUCUAUGUCUUCGUUAGCUCAAUAGAUUGCCAUGAUAUUUUUUUACCACGGCCCAUAACCUCUUUAAUGGCUUGGCAGCAGGACCUUUCCUUUGAUUGUUUCUUGAAGAUAUGAGAUCUAUAGUUCAGUUGUAUCGUUGGCUCUUAAGGGCCUGGAACAUGCAACAAUAGGGCUUCCGUUGUUGCAUGGCAAACAUGAGAAUUUUGCAUGGCCCUUACUGGGGAGUUUCCUCCUCAUUUGACUGAUGUGAGUAGAGACUCUUAGAGCCAGCCACCAUCAUAAUCAUCUACUAGAAUCCCAAGAUGCUUUCCCCAGCAGCUAAUAGCGCUGUUGUCUGUGGGUAGGGGGAAAACACCACCCUAACCCUGAAGAAUCCAUGACAUAGUGCUAUUACUUUGAUGUGAAUAAGUCUGGAAAAUAGUCUCUUUCUACUGUGGUUUGCUCUAUAAAAUCCUUGCCUCUGAAUUUUCCUGAAAACUAUGCUUUAUUCUGACUUACGGGUUAGACAAUUUUAGUGUAUUACCUGACUGCUUAACCGAUGGCUCUGAUGUGGUCAGUGACCUUGAACACGAAGAGAUGAAAAUCCUGAGGGAAGUUCUUAGAAAAUCAAAAGAGGAAUAUGACCAGGAAGAAGAAAGGAAGAGGAAAAAACAGUUAUCAGAGGCUAAAACAGAAGAGCCCACAGUGCAUUCCAGUGAAGCUGCAAUAAUGAAUAAUUCCCAAGGGGAUGGUGAACAUUUUGCACACCCACCCUCAGAAGUUAAAAUGCAUUUUGCUAAUCAGUCAAUAGAACCUUUGGGAAGAAAAGUGGAAAGGUCUGAAACUUCCUCCCUCCCACAAAAAGACCUGAAGAUUCCUGGCUUAGAGCAUGCGAGCAUUGAAGGACCAAUAGCAAACUUAUCAGUACUUGGAACAGAAGAACUUCGGCAACGAGAACACUAUCUCAAGCAGAAGAGAGAUAAGUUGAUGUCCAUGAGAAAGGAUAUGAGGACUAAACAGAUACAAAAUAUGGAGCAGAAAGGAAAACCCACUGGGGAGGUAGAGGAAAUGACAGAGAAACCAGAAAUGACAGCAGAGGAGAAGCAAACAUUACUAAAGAGGAGAUUGCUUGCAGAGAAACUCAAAGAAGAAGUUAUUAAUAAGUAAUAAUUAAGAACAAUUUAACAAAAUGGAAGUUCAAAUUGUCUUAAAAAUAAAUUAUUUAGUCCUUACACUGA